AGCGAGUGCGCGCUCCUCCUCGCCCGCCGCUAGGUCCAUCCCGGCCCAGCCACCAUGUCCAUCCACUUCAGCUCCCCGGUAUUCACCUCGCGCUCAGCCGCCUUCUCGGGCCGCGGCGCCCAGGUGCGCCUGAGCUCCGCUCGCCCCGGCGGCCUUGGCAGCAGCAGCCUCUACGGCCUCGGCGCCUCACGGCCGCGCGUGGCCGUGCGCUCUGCCUAUGGGGGCCCGGUGGGCGCCGGCAUCCGCGAGGUCACCAUUAACCAGAGCCUGCUGGCCCCGCUGCGGCUGGACGCCGACCCCUCCCUCCAGCGGGUGCGCCAGGAGGAGAGCGAGCAGAUCAAGACCCUCAACAACAAGUUUGCCUCCUUCAUCGACAAGGUGCGGUUUCUGGAGCAGCAGAACAAGCUGCUGGAGACCAAGUGGACGCUGCUGCAGGAGCAGAAGUCGGCCAAGAGCAGCCGCCUCCCAGACAUCUUUGAGGCCCAGAUUGCUGGCCUUCGGGGUCAGCUUGAGGCACUGCAGGUGGAUGGGGGCCGCCUGGAGGCGGAGCUGCGGAGCAUGCAGGAUGUGGUGGAGGACUUCAAGAAUAAGUACGAAGAUGAAAUUAACCACCGCACAGCUGCUGAGAAUGAGUUUGUGGUGCUGAAGAAGGAUGUGGAUGCUGCCUACAUGAGCAAGGUGGAGCUGGAGGCCAAGGUGGAUGCCCUGAAUGAUGAGAUCAACUUCCUCAGGACCCUCAAUGAGACGGAGUUGACAGAGCUGCAGUCCCAGAUCUCCGACACAUCUGUGGUGCUGUCCAUGGACAACAGUCGCUCCCUGGACCUGGACGGCAUCAUCGCUGAGGUCAAGGCGCAGUAUGAGGAGAUGGCCAAAUGCAGCCGGGCUGAGGCUGAAGCCUGGUACCAGACCAAGUUUGAGACCCUCCAGGCCCAGGCUGGGAAGCAUGGGGACGACCUCCGGAAUACCCGGAAUGAGAUUUCAGAGAUGAACCGGGCCAUCCAGAGGCUGCAGGCUGAGAUCGACAACAUCAAGAACCAGCGUGCCAAGUUGGAGGCCGCCAUUGCCGAGGCUGAGGAGCGUGGGGAGCUGGCGCUCAAGGAUGCUCGUGCCAAGCAGGAGGAGCUGGAAGCCGCCCUGCAGCGGGGCAAGCAGGAUAUGGCACGGCAGCUGCGUGAGUACCAGGAACUCAUGAGCGUGAAGCUGGCCCUGGACAUCGAGAUCGCCACCUACCGCAAGCUGCUGGAGGGCGAGGAGAGCCGAGUCUGCAAACUACGGCCACAUGCAGGCUUCCUGUUUGUCAAUCAAGUUUUCUUGGAACCCAGUCAUACCGCUUCCUUCAAGUAUUGCCUUUGGCUGUGGCUGCUUUACAUGACAACGGAGUGGAGCAGUUGAGGCAGAGACUACAUGGCCCACGAGCCUAAAGUUUUUACUAUCUGAAGCUCUAAGAAAAAGUUUGCCUGCCCAGAACCCCAAGCUGUUAUUUCAGGACCCACAAAAUGGAUUACUUACAGACAUUUACAGCACCAACGCCCUCACACAACCUUAUAGGGAAAGCAAAGAGACAGAAAUUAGUUGUGGGGAGCAAAGCUGGUGAAAUCUGUUUAACCUGCAAAUUCUCUCCUCCAAUUAGCGUUGAUGCACAUUCCAAGUAAAUAAUAUGCAGACAUGCUCCUGGGUGUUGAAGCACUGCAGCACUGCCUGGGGGAAACUGAGGGGACACCCUCCCCACAGCUGUGGUCCUCACCUCUGCUCCUCGCCCUCCAGCAGGCGCCUGUAGGUGGCGAUCUCAAAGUCCAGGCCAGCUUGGAGUUCAUCACCUCCUGGUACUCCCUGAUCAGGCAGGCCAUGUCCUGCUUGGCCUUCUGCAGGGCACCCUCCAGCUCGGCCAGCUUGCAGCGGGCAUCACUGAGGGCCGCCUCACCCUGCUGCUCAGACUGGGCCACCGCGGCCUCCAGCUUGGAGUUCUGGGAGGCAAGGGAGGGUUAUUAAGGAUCUCUGUUCUGGCUUCAGGGUCAGAGGCCAGGUAACCACUGACCACUGACUAGCAGAAGAAAAAGAGGCCUUGUCUAUUUGUUAGGCCAGGGGUUGCAAAUUAGUGCUCCCAGGCAUGUUUGCACAGUGUCUUCAAUUUUGGAAAUUUAACACAAUAAUUGAAAUUCUUGGCUUCUUUCAAAAGAUCAGAGGAUCUGGCCACACUGGACCUGCAUUUCUGCAUGGCCUGCCUCAGUUGGAUCUGCCUAGCCCUGCCUUUUGUGCUUUCCAGUUUACCAUAGUCCCUAUCAUACCCAAGUGCCUUGGGAACAGCUUGCUUGCUUCGCUCAUUUACUAACCCCAUUGAUGUCUGAAUGUGUGAUCACUGAUCUAGAACAACAGGCCAGAGAGGUUAAAUGCCUUUCCCAAGUCUCAUGGCAAACUAGUGGCAGAGCUUGUUUGAGAGCCCAGGUUUCCUGCCCCUUAGACUGGUGCUAUUUCCUCUGCCCCACUCUGCCCUUGGAAGCACCUCAUUCCCUCCAUAUUGCCCCAAUGCCUCCAUUCAGCGAGAAUGGAGAACGUUUUCCAUGGAGGAGGCUGUCUGUCCUCAUGCUGGGUGUUUGCCCUUGUCCCCACACACUGGCAAGGGGUCUAACCCAAAUCCCUCUCCUGAGGGCUAACCCCACUCUCUUCCUACACUGAGGGGUGGGCUGGGCUCCCAUACCUGGCACUUGGCGUUCUCCACCUCGGCUGUCAGCCUCUGGAUCAUGCGGUUCAGCUCGUUGAUCUCCUCCUUGGUGCGGCGCAGGGUCUCCCCGUGCCUGAUCACCGUGGCCUUCAUCUCCUCACACUGGGGAAGUAGAGUUGCUUAUGAGGCUCAGGGUGGGACCUCCCAUCCAUUCAGGACACCACGGAUGAUUGUGCAGGUUGUGCAGUGCUCAGCCUGUGCAACCACACAUGGCAGUCCUGCCCUGCUACCCCAACCUCAGAGAGGCAGCCCUUAUCUUCCCAUCCGUAGGGACCAGAAUCCCCAGAAAAGGAAGCCUAUUUAAUAGGUACCUUGCAUCCCUCCAACUGCCAUGUCUAGCAGGCAGGUGUCCUGUGCCACUCACCUUGCUGCGGUACCAGGACUCGGCCUCGGCCCGGCUGCGGGUGGCAAUGUCAUCGUACUGAGCUUUGAUCUCAGUGAUGACACAGUGCAUGUUCAGGUCCCGACUGUUGUCCAUCUUGACGACCACUGAGGUGUCUGAGAUGUGCGACUGGAGAACGCGGAUCUCCUGCAGGAGAUGGGGAGUGGCAAGAGCUUCUUAGACCAGAGCCCUACUCUUGGUAGCCCACCCUCAUCAUCAUCCCUUGUCCCCUUUCCCUGCUUCUUCGAUGUCUGAAGCCCCACCCUCCCAGUUACAGUCUUCCACCUCAACCCUGGGACCCCCUCAGGACUCCUCAAGCCCAGAGUCCUGAGCCUAGAGGACUUGGAGGUAGAGAGUCCAUGUCUGAGGCCCAGUGCCUGAUUUUAAUCAGGACCUUCCAGCUUGAACCUUUGGGUCUAGGACCAGAGUUUACCACCUUGUGGCAAUUGUCACUUUAGUAACCAGGAACACCAGGUUGCCUGGGGCAUGGCAGUGGGAGGUCAAGCCACACUUCUUCACCUGCUCAUGGUGAACCUGCCUGGGGUUUCUCCCCUUGUCCCACCAUAGGGUCAGAAGCUGAAUGGUGACAAGUAUUUUCCAAUGUCUAACUCAUAUCCUCCUUGCUGCCCCGCUGCUUUGUGACCCCGCACCUCCUCAUAUAGCCGCCUCAGGAAGUCGAUCUCCUGGGUCAGGGCCUCCACGUUGGCCUCUAGGUCUGAUUUGCGCAGGUAGGCACAGUCCACAUCCUAAAGGGGAGAAGGUGGCACAGGAAUUGCACUGGGAGACAAUUCAGAACCCUUGUUUUUUUCCUACCAGGGAGGGGCACCCCAUCAGGCUGAGCAGCUUCCCUGGAAACCCUCUGUACGUGCUCAUCCCAGUGCCUGGUAUCAUGCCUUGGUGAAGCCCCUUAUACAGUUAGUAGUGGCGUCAAGAGCAGGUUUGGGUAAGGGAGGGGGACACUGAGGUUUGCAGGUACUUCCUCUGGCACCCACUGGGAUGAUUUCUCUAGAAUCCAUGUCAUGCACUAUCACCAAAACUUAAGAUCUGGUGUACAGUGGGUAAAUUCUAAUGAUGCCCCACCCCUCUCCGCUCUGGAAUCUCAUGGAAGAUAAUCUAGAUCUGUGGUCAGAAGAGGGCUCAGGGCUCAACUCUGUCCCUUCCAAGUCAGUGUCACUCUGAGCAGCCCCCUUAACCUCUGCACCUCAUUUUCUCACAAUAACCCCUGCUUUCCUCAUAUGGAGGUGGCUGGAAGGGCCUAAUGAGAGUCCAGGCACUUGUACAGAGUCAAGUCUAAGAGGCAAGGAAUGACGGUCACUGCCCCUGCCUGUGGUUCUGAGCUGUUGCUGGCCUGAGGAUGCAGCCAUUGUCUAUAAUUCACCUGCUCUUUCACUCGCAAAUAUUUACAGGGUGCCUACUCUAUGCCAGGCGCAGGGCCGAAGGAGGUGAAAAUCUGGUGGCUAUAUGGCAGCAACCUCAGAUGGGGGAGAAUAUUGCCCUGCCUGAAGCAGGCAGUGUAUUCUGCUGCCAGAGGCACCCAGGGAGCACUGGAGCACUGGGGAAAGGAACAGAAAGAAGCUGGGCCGUGUGAUUCUAAGGGAGUCCCUCCACCUCUCCGAACUACAGAGAGCCUGAUGUUAGUCAAGGUCUCCCAGCUCAAACCUUUGGGUCUAGGACCCUUCUGUCUCUGGCCUCCAUUCUGAGUUAGGGGACAAGGAUUCUGGGGUCACUCACCUUCUUCAAGGCCACAAAUUCAUUCUCAGCAGUGGCCCUUAGUGCCACCUCUUCUUCAUACCUGGGGACAAAACACACAAGGCUCAGAUCUGGGGAGGAAAAAAAAUGGGAAUGAAGGCACAGGCAAACACAUUCCGGGAACUGGAUCUUUUGGAGGUGGUCACAAGAAUCAAAAAAGUGUUGGACUGAAGGGAACUUGUCCAUCCCUUUCUUCUGGGCAUUCAAACCAACCCAUGUUACUCAAAGCUCUUUCUAUUUCAGGGACUUUCAUUCCUGAUGUGGGUCAGGGUGGGGGCCCUGCACAUUUUCGAAGACCUCCUCUCUGUUUCUGGGCUGUAACUCCUUUGGGGCAGGAACCCUGCCCAGUUCUGGUACCUCUCCUUUCUCCUCCUUCUUACUUCCUUACUCCUUUCCCACUCAGAGCCCAACAUAGCACCUACAACAUUGAGUAGAUGCUCAAUAAAAUGUUUGAUGAAUUAAUGAAAUAAACAUAAUGAUGAAGUA